AGCGCGUAACGAGAGACUGCUUGCUGCGGCAGAGACGCCAGAGGUGCAGCUCCAGCAGCAAUGGCAGUGACGGCGUUGGCGGCGCGGACGUGGCUUGGCGUGUGGGGCGUGAGGACCAUGCAAGCCCGAGGCUUCGGCUCGGAUCAGUCCGAGAAUGUCGACCGGGGCGCGGGCUCCAUCCGGGAAGCCGGUGGGGCCUUCGGAAAGAGAGAGCAGGCUGAAGAGGAACGAUAUUUCCGGUGAGGCUCACCGGGUCCCAAGUCCAGCCCUGGAUCUCCCAAUGGCCUUCCAAUCCUUAAACUGCCAAUCGCCCCACCCGUUCCUACCUGGUGCCUUGGGCGCCCCAUCCCCCAACAGAACUCCCGGGCCCCAAUCCAGUAUACCCUAACCCUUGAUGUCCCGACCGUUGCCACGUAUAGGGCACUCCCAGUUACCUGCACAACAGUUUCAGGCCCCCAAACCGUUUCCACCGGCGGGUCUCCAAAACAACCCACGGCUCAACUCCUCCUUUAUCAUUACCAUCUCCCGCGUGGAGUUCUCCUCAGGUCGUGCGAAACACCCCCAGAUUCUUCGCACAGUGUCUAGAUCCGACCGCCCAACGUUUGCCUCCCAGCCUGACUCCCUCGGCCCUUACCCACCUGUCACCCCCUCUACGCUCUCCUUCCUCGCCAGCACGCCUUAGCUUUGCAAGCCUGCAUGCAUUCAGGCUUCUCAGGUGUUUCUAGACCCCCGACUCCGCAAGAGUGAGGAUGAUGGGAGCUGGUCAUGGGAGCUACUUAUGGUUGGACACCAUCUUCUAAAGGCUUUUGCCCUACUCAGCCCAACCUAGACCUGUAGAUUUCCCUCUCCUGCUUAGGAGUAUGGAGUGGGCUGGGCCUCCCUUUGCCAGCCUUGAGUUAUCUUUAACUGACUUCUGUCCACUCUGGAGAGCAGUGAGGAAUUAAUCUUGCUUUUGCUUGUCCUUUGGCCUUUCACUUCUGCCUUCUGUUGAGAAUUAUCACCAUGACACCUGCCAUACCGUAUAGAGAGCCAAGGUACAGCCGUUAGAGACUAUCUAAUUGAGCCCCUACAUUUUGUAGUUAAGGAAAACUGAGGCCUAAAUGUGACCAAACCAACAUUGUAAUCCAGUCCCUUCUUGGAACCUAAAUUGAACUGCCAAGUACUGCGCAUGCAAGAGACCCUUUAUUGGCCUUACAGUGGGCCAUUCAUUUCUAUAGGCAAAGAAAGCUCUAGACAGAUUGGAAUAGGAAAUGGAUAUUUGCCUUUUAGCUACACCCCUUUGUCUGUCUUCCUCAUUUUGUUCCUUUUUUUUUCCCUAAAGGGGAGUCAAGUUCCCUGGGUUGUUCCCCUCAUAAGGUAUUAGGGACUUGUGUCACAUCUCUCUGGAGUUUUCUAUUUUAAAGAGGAAUCUGAAAGCAAUAAGCUCUUUGGUCUUCUUAAGAUGGCUACACCUCAAUUUAAGAUGGGGUAUUCUUUCACUAGUUGAGGAGUAGAAGAGGAUGACCAGCUAGACUCCCAUGGAAUUGGAACUCCUAUUCCUUGCUUAGACAUUACAGGUUAUGCUUUGAGAUCUCUUUGGGGUGAAGGAUUGAAAUUAAACCCUGAGCCACCGUGUCCUUGUAGAGCACAGAGUAGAGAACAACUGGCAGCUUUGAAAAAACACCAUGAAGAAGAAAUCGUUCAUCAUAAGAAGGAGAUUGAGCGUCUGCAGAAAGAAAUUGAGCGCCAUAAGCAGAAGAUCAAAAUGCUAAAACAUGAUGAUUAAGUGCACACCGUGUGCCAUAGAAUGGCACAUGUCAUUGCCCACUUCUGUGUAGACAUGGUUCUGGUUUAACUAAUAUUUGUCUGUGUGCUACUAACAGAUUAUAAUAAAUUGUCAUCAGUGAA